CCAUAAUCUCAUACAUAGGACAGUUUCCAUUGCAUACCUUUGUCUUUCUGCACAUAAAAUUUAAAUUUUUGUUAUUCUAAAACACUUCUGUCUUAUGCUGAAGUAUAUACUUAAGAUACACUACUACUCAAUGCUGGGUUUUUUUUUGUUUGUUUUAAUGUGCAUAUAAAUUAUAAUAGAGGUGAGGUGCUGCUCAGGCUGGUCUUGAAUGCCUGGCCUGAAGUGAUUCUCUCACCUUGGCCUCCCAAAGUGCUGGGAUUACAGGCAUGGGCCACCAUGCCUGGCCAUGAUUUUUUUUUUCCCUGUCUCUGGCAUUGUAUACUUUUUUUAAUGCCUUCUUACAUAAUUGCUCUGGUUAGUCUGUGCAGUCAUUUUUUUGAUUUAACUGUAGGAGGGGAAAAAUCAGUAAUCUUAAUAAAGAAUCAUAGAAAUGUUUUAUUUUAAGAUACCUUUAAGGUUUCUAAAUCAUAUGCAGUGUAUUUCCUUGAGGUCAGUUUAACAUCUUUCCUUAGGGAAUUCAUGUAAGACUUUUAGGCGAGUUUUUUCUCUUUGAUUCCCUUGGAGAUUUUAAACCAGCUGCUACUUAUUUAACUAGUCUGUGCCUUCUAUCCUUGUGAUAUACAUGUUCUUGCUUCAGUUUUUAUAUUUUUCUGUACUUCUAAAAUAAAUCGUUCUUUUAUAGCCUCCACUGAAGAUCUUUCUCUAUACAUCCCCAAAUAUUUGGUAAACUACGUGUCUUAGGUUGUAAGUGCCGUAAAAAUAAAGCAUGGCCUUGGCUGAACAUCAGUGUUUACAUAGAAAGUGGAUUAGUUUGGUAUUAGGAAGGUUUUUUUUUUUUCUUUUUUCUUUCUUUUUUUUUUUUUUAAGACAGAGUCUCGCUCUGUCACCAGGCUGGAAUGCAGUUGCGCGAUCUCGGCUCACUGCAACCGCCGCCUCCCGGUCAAGCGGUUCUCCUGCCUCAGCCUCCCAAGUAGCUGGGACUACGGGCAUGCGCCACCAUGCCCUGCUAAUUUUUUUGUAUUUUCAGUAGAGACGGGAUUUCACUGUGUUGGCCAGGAUGGUCUUGAUUUCUUGACCUCAUGAUCUGCCCGCCUCGGCCUCCCAAAGUGCUGGGAUUACAGGCACGAGCCUUUUUGUUCAUUAUGUUGUAAUAUUAAUAACUCAUGACAAGCCUGUUUUUAAGAUUAUAAAAUGGUUUUCUAAAGCCAAAUUUUAAUUAAUUGUACCUGAAGAGCAGCUUGAAAACAUGGCUCUUAAGUAUGCAGGAUAGCAGACAUUCAGGGCAGGGUGCUUUCCAUUAGGAACUGCCUAAUAAGACUAGGAAAAAUCUUUAUUGCUAAGAGGACCUAGCAGUGUAUAUAUUCAGGGUAGAGAAGUAUAAUGAAGAACAACGGUCCCCUUGUAUUCUGAUAGCAUAUGGCAUUUAUGCAGGUUUCUGACAGUUAGAUGUGAUUGUUAAAUUACAGUCUUGAAAAAUGUUAUAUUCUCCCCCUGUGUUUACAGGCAGAAAUUGAUACUACCUUGAGAAGAGUCACAUGGUAUUUUCCCAAAAGAGCCAAGAUAAAGAACCUUCAAUUCUACAUAAUGAGAUGGAAACAAUAUGAAGCAUAUGUACAAGCUUUGGAGGGCAAGUACACAGAUCUUAACUCUAAUGAUGUAACUGGCCUAAGAGAGUCUGAAGAAAAACUAAAGCAACAACAGCAGGAGUCUGCACGCAGGGAAAACAUCCUUGUAAUGCGACUAGCAACCAAGGAACAAGAGAUGCAAGAGUGUACUACUCAAAUCCAGUACCUCAAGCAAGUCCAGCAGCCGAGCGUUGCCCAACUGAGAUCAACAAUGGUAGACCCAGCGAUCAACUUGUUUUUCCUAAAAAUGAAAGGUGAACUGGAACAGACUAAAGACAAACUGGAACAAGCCCAAAAUGAACUGAGUGCCUGGAAGUUUACGCCUGAUAGCCAAACAGGGAAAAAGUUAAUGGCGAAGUGUCGAAUGCUUAUCCAGGAGAAUCAAGAGCUUGGAAGGCAGCUGUCCCAGGGACGUAUUGCACAACUUGAAGCAGAGUUGGCUUUACAGAAGAAAUACAGUGAGGAGCUUAAAAGCAGUCAGGAUGAACUGAAUGACUUCAUCAUCCAGCUUGAUGAAGAAGUAGAGGGUAUGCAGAGUACCAUUCUAGUUCUGCAGCAGCAGCUGAAGGAGACACGCCAGCAGUUGGCUCAGUACCAGCAGCAGCAGUCUCAGGCCUCUGCCCCAAGUACCAGCAGGACUACAGCUUCUGAACCUGUAGAACAGUCAGAGGCCACAAGUAAAGACUGCAGUCGUCUGACAAACGGACCAAGUAAUGGUAGCUCCUCCCGCCAGAGGACGUCUGGGUCUGGAUUUCACAGGGAGGGCAACACAACCGAAGAUGACUUUCCUUCUUCUCCAGGGAAUGGUAAUAAGUCCUCCAACAGCUCAGAGGAGAGAACUGGCAGAGGAGGUAGUGGUUACGUAAAUCAACUCAGUGCGGGGUAUGAAAGUGUAGACUCUCCCACGGGCAGUGAAAACUCUCUCACACACCAAUCAAAUGACACAGACUCCAGUCAUGACCCUCAAGAGGAGAAAGCAGUGAGUGGGAAAGGUAAUCGAACUGUGGGUUCCCGCCACGUUCAGAAUGGCUUGGACUCAAGUGUAAAUGUACAGGGUUCAGUUUUGUAAUAUUUUUUCAGCAAAUUUUUAUACAGUGUCAUUUAAUUUGGGAGAGGAUACUGUCCAGAAAAUUAAUGCAUACUUUUGUCACAAUUUGCCUUUUUGUGGGUGUACGUUUUGGUUUUUUUUUGUUGUUUUUUUUCUUUGUUUUUUUUUUCUUUUCUUUUUUUUUUUUUUUUUUUUUUUUUGCUUCAAUACUUCUGCCGCUUUGGAAAUUGUAACAGUUAAUUACUUUGAAUGUUGCUAAAAGGACAUUUUGUGUAGGGUCAAGUUAUUUUUAUAUGAGUUAAUGUGAAAUUGUAAAUGGAAAUUUUUCCUUAAAAUACAACACAAUGAUGUCUGUAUAAAUCUGUCUGUUUAGAAUCUGUGCUGUGUAAGGGCAUUCGUACUCAUGCUGUUACUGUACUUAUGCACCAUUCAGACUUGUUAGAGUAGAUGUGGGUUUAUGACUGCCAAGUUUGCCCAGUACAGUAGUUUUUUAUCACUAAAAGUUGGACUCAUUGAUGGAGUCCUGUAGUAGUUUCAGUGUUAGAUACAGUUUUUUCCACCAUACAUCUGUGCAUUUUCUCUUUAGGUGACUGUUUAAGAAAUUUGUGUGCAUAGUUACUCAGUUUUUAUGAACUGUUGUAUCCUGUUAAUGCAUAUUGCUCUGUGACUCCAGUAUAUCUUACCUGUACUGACCAAACCUAAAUAAAGAUUUUUAUUGUAACUCCUUAA